GAAGACGCGUCGUUGGGUUUUGGAGGCCGUGAAACAGCCGUUUGAGUUUGGCUGCGGGUGGAGAACGUUUGUCAGGGGCCCGGCCAAGAAGGAGGCCCGCCUGUUACGAUGGUGUCCAUGAGUUUCAAGCGGAACCGCAGUGACCGGUUCUACAGCACCCGGUGCUGCGGCUGUUGCCAUGUCCGCACCGGGACGAUCAUCCUGGGGACCUGGUACAUGGUAGUAAACCUAUUGAUGGCAAUUUUGCUGACUGUGGAAGUGACUCAUCCAAACUCCAUGCCAGCUGUCAACAUUCAGUAUGAAGUCAUCGGUAAUUACUAUUCGUCUGAGAGAAUGGCUGAUAAUGCCUGUGUUCUUUUUGCCGUCUCUGUUCUUAUGUUUAUAAUCAGUUCAAUGCUGGUUUAUGGAGCAAUUUCUUAUCAAGUGGGUUGGCUGAUUCCAUUCUUCUGUUACCGACUUUUUGACUUCGUCCUCAGUUGCCUGGUUGCUAUUAGUUCUCUCACCUAUUUGCCAAGAAUCAAAGAAUAUCUGGAUCAACUACCUGAUUUUCCCUACAAAGAUGACCUCCUGGCCUUGGACUCCAGCUGCCUCCUGUUCAUUGUUCUUGUGUUCUUUGCCUUAUUCAUCAUUUUUAAGGCUUAUCUAAUUAACUGUGUUUGGAACUGCUAUAAAUACAUCAACAACCGAAACGUGCCGGAGAUUGCUGUGUACCCUGCCUUUGAAGCACCUCCUCAGUACGUUUUGCCAACCUAUGAAAUGGCCGUGAAAAUGCCUGAAAAAGAACCACCACCUCCUUACUUACCUGCCUGAAGAAAUUCUGCCUUUGACAAUAAAUCCUAUACCAGCUUUUUGUUUGUUUAUGUUACAGAAUGCUGCAAUUCAGGGCUCUUCAAACUUGUUUGAUAUAAAAUAUGUUGUCUUUUGUUUAAGCAUUUAUUUUCAAACACUAAGGAGCUUUUUGACAUCUGUUAAACGUCUUUUUGUUUUUUUGUUAAGUCUUUUACAUUUUAAUAGUUUUUGAAGACAAUCUAGGUUAAGCAAGAGCAAAGUGCCAUUGUUUGCCUUUAAUUGGGGGGUGGGAAGGGAAAGAGGGUACUUGCCACAUAGUUUCCUUUUUAACUGCACUUUCUUUAUAUAAUCGUUUGCAUUUUGUUACUUGCUACCCUGAGUACUUUCAGGAAGACUGACUUAAAUAUUCGGGGUGAGUAAGUAGUUGGGUAUAAGAUCUGAACUUUUCAUCUGCAGAGGCAAGAAAAAUAUUUGACAUUGUGACUUGACUGUGGAAGAUGAUGGUUGCAUGUUUCUAGUUUGUAUAUGUUUCCAUCUUUGUGAUAAGAUGAUUUAAUAAAUCUCUUUAAAUACUUA